GACUCUUACUGUUUCUCAUGGUGAGAAGACAAUAUUUGCUUUCUCUUUUUCCUUUCUUCCGGAUGAGAGGCUAAGCCAUAAUAGAAAGAAUGGAGAAUUAUUGAUUGACCGUCUUUAUUCUGUGGGCUCUGAUUCUCCAAUGGGAAUACCAAGGGAUAUUAUUUUUACAGAUGGUUUUCCAUACUGGAACCCAAAGGUAAAGACACUCAAGGACAGACAUUUUUGGCAGAGAUGAAAAUGGCAAGUUCCCUGGCUUUCCUUCUGCUCAACUUUCAUGUCUCCCUCCUCUUGGUCCAGCUGCUCACUCCUUGCUCAGCUCAGUUUUCUGUGCUUGGACCCUCUGGGCCCAUCCUGGCCAUGGUGGGUGAAGACGCUGAUCUGCCCUGUCACCUGUUCCCGACCAUGAGUGCAGAGACCAUGGAGCUGAAGUGGGUAAGUUCCAGCCUAAGGCAGGUGGUGAACGUGUAUGCAGAUGGAAAGGAAGUGGAAGACAGGCAGAGUGCACCGUAUCGAGGGAGAACUUCGAUUCUGCGGGAUGGCAUCACUGCAGGGAAGGCUGCUCUCCGAAUACACAACGUCACAGCCUCUGACAGUGGAAAGUACUUGUGUUAUUUCCAAGAUGGUGACUUCUAUGAAAAAGCCCUGGUGGAGCUGAAGGUUGCAGCACUGGGUUCUAAUCUUCACGUCGAAGUGAAGGGUUAUGAGGAUGGAGGGAUCCAUCUGGAGUGCAGGUCCACCGGCUGGUACCCCCAACCCCAAAUACAGUGGAGCAACGCCAAGGGAGAGAACAUCCCAGCUGUGGAAGCACCUGUGGUUGCAGAUGGAGUGGGCCUAUAUGAAGUAGCAGCAUCUGUGAUCAUGAGAGGCGGCUCCGGGGAGGGUGUAUCCUGCAUCAUCAGAAAUUCCCUCCUCGGCCUGGAAAAGACAGCCAGCAUUUCCAUCGCAGACCCCUUCUUCAGGAGCGCCCAGCCCUGGAUCGCAGCCCUGGCAGGGACCCUGCCUAUCUUGCUGCUGCUUCUCGCCGGAGCCAGUUACUUCUUGUGGAGACAACAGAAGGAAAUAACUGCUCUGUCCAGUGAGAUAGAAAGUGAGCAAGAGAUGAAAGAAAUGGGAUAUGCUGCAACAGAGCGGGAAAUAAGCCUAAGAGAGAGCCUCCAGGAGGAACUCAAGAGGAAAAAAAUCCAGUACUUGACUCGUGGAGAGGAGUCUUCGUCCGAUACCAAUAAGUCAGCCUGAUGCUCUAAUGGAAAAAUGGCCCUCUUCAAGCCUGGGCCUCCCAUUGGCCAAACACAGCAGCAAACCAGAGGACAAGGGAGCCCAGUGGCACUGUCCAUAGAGGACAGAUUCCUGGGGUCCAGAAGAGGGUGGAGAAAGCUGAAGGCUGGAGAGUGAAUCUAGGGCAUAUAAGGCCCCACACAGAGCCCAGCACAGAGACGGCCUUGCAGCUAUCAGGAAGAUGAGGAGCUUCCUUCAUGGCCUGCUGUGGGCUGAGUAAAUAAUAUGAUUGCCUUCUACAGCGCUAGAGAUUCAUAUGUUUAUCCCCAUUUUUCAGGUGAGGAAAUGCUUCAGAUGAGGCUCCACCUUGUUAAAUAAAUUGGAUGUAUGGAAAAAUAGACUGCAGAAAAGGGGAACUCAUUUAGCUCACGAGUGGUCGAGUGAAGAUUGAAAAUUAACCUCUGAGGGCCAGCACAGCAGCUCAUGCCUGUAAUCCUAGCACUUUGGAAGGCUGAGGAGGGCGGAUCACAAGGUCAGGAGAUCAAGACCAUCCUGGCUAACACGGUGAAACCCCGUCUCUACUAAAAAUACAAAAAAUAAAAAAUUAGCCGGGCAUGGUGACGGGCACCUGUAGUCCCAGCUACUCGGGAGGCUGAGGCAGGAGAAUGGCAUGAACCCGGAAGGCAGAGCUUGCAGUGAGCCGAGAUCACGCCACUGCACUCCAGCCUGGGAGACAGAGCGAGACUCUGUCUCAAGAAAAAAAAAAAAAAAAAAAAAGAAAAGAAAAUUAACCUCUGAGUAUAAAGCAUCAGUGGGCAGAAUCAAUGUGGGGAGGGAAACAACAAAAAUGUAGAAAGAGGAUCCUUGUUGCUUCUUGGGGCCGCAUCAGGGUAUUGGGUUAGGCAGAUACUGACCUUACUUUCAUUUCCCCUCUGGUCACUAGACCCCUGGGGCUUUCACCAAUGACAUUGAUGAGAGAAUCACAUUCAGGGCAGGCUAGGGACACGGGGUUCUGGAAGGACCUCCUCAGCAUGGCCCAAGCCUUGCAUGCUGUGGCUCUUAAAUCCAGGAAAAAUGGCUGACCCCAUGGACACCUCCUCAAACUCUCUGCAGCAGAUGUAAUUCUGUAUCCAGACAUGGCAAAUGCCAUCCUCCUUGUUUCUGAGGACCAGAGGAGUGUACAGCGUGCUGAGGAGCCCCAUGACCUACCAGACAACCCUGAGAGAUUUGAAUGGCGUUACUGUGUGCUUGGCUGUGAAAGCUUCAUGUCAGAGAGACACUACUGGGAGGUGGAAGUGGGGGACAGAAAAGAGUGGCAUAUUGGGGUAUGUAGUAAGAACGUGGAGAGGAAAAAAGUUUGGGUCAAAAUGACACCGGAGAACGGAUACUGGACUAUGGGCCUGACUGAUGGGAAUAAGUAUCGGGCUCUCACUGAGCCCAGAACCAACCUGAAACUUCCUGAGCCUCCUAGGAAAGUGGGGGUCAUCCUGGACUAUGAGACUGGACAUAUCUCGUUCUACAAUGCCACGGAUGGAUCUCAUAUCUACACAUUUCUGCACGCCUCUUCCUCUGAGCCUCUGUAUCCUGUAUUCAGAAUUUUGACCUUGGAGCCCACUGCCCUGACCGUUUGCCCAAUACCAAAAGUAGAGAGUUCCCCCGAUCCCGACCUAGUGCCUGAUCAUUCCCUGGAGAUACCACUGACCCCAGGCUUAGCUAAUGAAAGUGGGGAGCCUCAGGCUGAAGUAACAUCUCUGCUUCUCCCUGCCCAGCCUGGAGCUAAGGGUCUCACCCUCCACAACAGCCAGUCAGAACCAUAAAGCUACAGGCACACACUGAAGCACUUUACUGAUAUUCAUUCAAUUAUUCCAUAGGACAGUUGUUUGAGUUUGGUGCCACCUUAUUGGCCCCUUUAUACAGAUAAGGAAACUGGGGUGUAGAAAAGUGUAUUGACUUUACAAAGCAGACAGGAAUAGUGAACAACAGAGCUGGGAUCUGAACAACAAUGACUAACAUUAAUGGAGAAUUUAAAACGUUCUGAGUGCUGUGUUAUGAGCUUUGGUGGGUGUCACUCCUUUAAUCCUCACAACACCCUGUCAGGUAGUCUCAUUUGGCAAGUAUGGAAGCAGAGGCAGGGCAACAUUAAGUAGCUUACAUAACUCACACGGUAAUUUGUGCAGUUGGGAGAUGUUCAGCUUCAGUCCCUGGCCAAUUGCCCGUUCUUUUCCAGCCUGAUUUUUCCUGCAUGGGAAGAGCCCACAUGUAGCCCUGAGGUUCCCUUCCCAGGACAGCUCCAGGAUCGAGAUCACUGUGAGUGGUUGUGGAGUUAAGACCCCUAUGGACUCCUUCCCAGCUGAUUAUCAGAGCCUUAGACCCAGCACUCCUUGGAUUGGCUCUGCAGAGUGUCUUGGUUGAGAGAAUAACGUUGCAGUUCCCACAGGGCAUGUGACUUUGAAAGAGACUAGAGGCCACACUCAGUUAAUAAUGGGGCACAGAUGUGUUCCCACCCAACAAAUGUGAUAAGUGAUCGUGCAGCCAGAGCCAGCCUUCCUUCAGUCAAGGUUUCCAGGCAGAGCAAAUACCCUAGAGAUUCUCUGUAAUAUUGGUAAUUUGGAUGAAGGAAGCUAGAAGAAUUACAGGGAUGUUUUUAAUCCCACUAUGGACUCAGUCUCCUGGAAAAGGAUCUGUCCACUCCUGGUCAUUGGUGGAUGUUAAACCCAUAUUCCUUUCAACUGCUGCCUGCUAGGGAAAACUGCUCCUCAUUAUCAUCACUAUUAUUGCUCACCACUGUAUCCCCUCUACUGGGCAAGUGCUUGUCAAGUUCUAGUUGUUCAAUAAAUUUGUUAAUAAUGCUGA